GUUGCCGGCCCCUGAAGUGGAGCGAGAGGGAGGUGCUUCGCCGUUUCUCCUGCCAGGGGAGGUCCCGGCUUCCCGUGGAGGCUCCGGACCAAGCCCCUUCAGCUUCUCCCUCCGGAUCGAUGUGCUGCUGUUAACCCGUGAGGAGGCGGCGGCGGCGGCAGCGGCAGCGGAAGAUGGUGUUGCUGAGAGUGUUAAUUCUGCUCCUCUCCUGGGCGGCGGGGAUGGGAGGUCAGUAUGGGAAUCCUUUAAAUAAAUAUAUCAGACAUUAUGAAGGAUUAUCUUACAAUGUGGAUUCAUUACACCAAAAACACCAGCGUGCCAAAAGAGCAGUCUCACAUGAAGACCAAUUUUUACGUCUAGAUUUCCAUGCCCAUGGAAGACAUUUCAACCUACGAAUGAAGAGGGACACUUCCCUUUUCAGUGAUGAAUUUAAAGUAGAAACAUCAAAUAAAGUACUUGAUUAUGAUACCUCUCAUAUUUACACUGGACAUAUUUAUGGUGAAGAAGGAAGUUUUAGCCAUGGGUCUGUUAUUGAUGGAAGAUUUGAAGGAUUCAUCCAGACUCGUGGUGGCACAUUUUAUGUUGAGCCAGCAGAGAGAUAUAUUAAAGACCGAACUCUGCCAUUUCACUCUGUCAUUUAUCAUGAAGAUGAUAUUAACUAUCCCCAUAAAUACGGUCCUCAGGGGGGCUGUGCAGAUCAUUCAGUAUUUGAAAGAAUGAGGAAAUACCAGAUGACUGGUGUAGAGGAAGUAACACAGAUACCUCAAGAAGAACAUGCUGCUAAUGGUCCAGAACUUCUGAGGAAAAAACGUACAACUUCAGCUGAAAAAAAUACUUGUCAGCUUUAUAUUCAGACUGAUCAUUUGUUCUUUAAAUAUUACGGAACACGAGAAGCUGUGAUUGCCCAGAUAUCCAGUCAUGUUAAAGCGAUUGAUACAAUUUACCAGACCACAGACUUCUCCGGAAUCCGUAACAUCAGUUUCAUGGUGAAACGCAUAAGAAUCAAUACAACUGCUGAUGAGAAGGACCCUACAAAUCCUUUCCGUUUCCCAAAUAUUGGUGUGGAGAAGUUUCUGGAAUUGAAUUCUGAGCAGAAUCAUGAUGACUACUGUUUGGCCUAUGUCUUCACAGACCGAGAUUUUGAUGAUGGCGUACUUGGUCUGGCUUGGGUUGGAGCACCUUCAGGAAGCUCUGGAGGAAUAUGUGAAAAAAGUAAACUCUAUUCAGAUGGUAAGAAGAAGUCCUUAAACACUGGAAUUAUUACUGUUCAGAACUAUGGGUCUCAUGUACCUCCCAAAGUCUCUCACAUUACUUUUGCUCACGAAGUUGGACAUAACUUUGGAUCCCCACAUGAUUCUGGAACAGAGUGCACACCAGGAGAAUCUAAGAAUUUGGGUCAAAAAGAAAAUGGCAAUUACAUCAUGUAUGCAAGAGCAACAUCUGGGGACAAACUUAACAACAAUAAAUUCUCACUCUGUAGUAUUAGAAAUAUAAGCCAAGUUCUUGAGAAGAAGAGAAACAACUGUUUUGUUGAAUCUGGCCAACCUAUUUGUGGAAAUGGAAUGGUAGAACAAGGUGAAGAAUGUGAUUGUGGCUAUAGUGACCAGUGUAAAGAUGAAUGCUGCUUCGAUGCAAAUCAACCAGAGGGAAGAAAAUGCAAACUGAAACCUGGGAAACAGUGCAGUCCAAGUCAAGGUCCUUGUUGUACAGCACAGUGUGCAUUCAAGUCAAAGUCUGAGAAGUGUCGGGAUGAUUCAGACUGUGCAAGGGAAGGAAUAUGUAAUGGCUUCACAGCUCUCUGCCCAGCAUCUGACCCUAAACCAAACUUCACAGACUGUAAUAGGCAUACACAAGUGUGCAUUAAUGGGCAAUGUGCAGGUUCUAUCUGUGAGAAAUAUGGCUUAGAGGAGUGUACGUGUGCCAGUUCUGAUGGCAAAGAUGAUAAAGAAUUAUGCCAUGUAUGCUGUAUGAAGAAAAUGGACCCAUCAACUUGUGCCAGUACAGGGUCUGUGCAGUGGAGUAGGCACUUCAGUGGUCGAACCAUCACCCUGCAACCUGGAUCCCCUUGCAACGAUUUUAGAGGUUACUGUGAUGUUUUCAUGCGGUGCAGAUUAGUAGAUGCUGAUGGUCCUCUAGCUAGGCUUAAAAAAGCAAUUUUUAGUCCAGAGCUCUAUGAAAACAUUGCUGAAUGGAUUGUGGCUCAUUGGUGGGCAGUAUUACUUAUGGGAAUUGCUCUGAUCAUGCUAAUGGCUGGAUUUAUUAAGAUAUGCAGUGUUCAUACUCCAAGUAGUAAUCCAAAGUUGCCUCCUCCUAAACCACUUCCAGGCACUUUAAAGAGGAGGAGACCUCCACAGCCCAUUCAGCAACCCCAGCGUCAGCGGCCCCGAGAGAGUUAUCAAAUGGGACACAUGAGACGCUAACUGCAGCUUUUGCCUUGGUUCUUCCUAGUGCCUACAAUGGGAAAACUUCACUCCAAAGAGAAACCUAUUAAGUCAUCAUCUCCAAACUAAACCCUCACAAGUAACAGUUGAAGAAAAAAUGGCAAGAGAUCAUAUCCUCAGACCAGGUGGAAUUACUUAAAUUUUAAAGCCUGAAAAUUCCAAUUUGGGGGUGGGAGGUGGAAAAGGAACCCAAUUUUCUUAUGAACAGAUAUUUUUAACUUAAUGGCACAAAGUCUUAGAAUAUUAUUAUGUGCCCCGUGUUCCCUGUUCUUCGUUGCUGCAUUUUCUUCACUUGCAGGCAAACUUGGCUCUCAAUAAACUUUUACCACAAAUUGAAAUAAAUAUAUUUUUUUCAACUGCCAAUCAAGGCUAGGAGGCUCGACCACCUCAACAUUGGAGACAUCACUUGCCAAUGUACAUACCUUGUUAUAUGCAGACAUGUAUUUCUUACGUACACUGUACUUCUGUGUGCAAUUGUAAACAGAAAUUGCAAUAUGGAUGUUUCUUUGUAUUAUAAAAUUUUUCCGCUCUUAAUUAAAAAUUACUGUUUAAUUGACAUACUCAGGAUAACAGAGAAUGGUGGUAUUCAGUGGUCCAGGAUUCUGUAAUGCUUUACACAGGCAGUUUUGAAAUGAAAAUCAAUUUACCUUUCUGUUACGAUGGAGUUGGUUUUGAUACUCAUUUUUUCUUUAUCACAUGGCUGCUACGGGCACAAGUGACUAUACUGAAGAACACAGUUAAGUGUUGUGCAAACUGGACAUAGCAGCACAUACUACUUCAGAGUUCAUGAUGUAGAUGUCUGGUUUCUGCUUACGUCUUUUAAACUUUCUAAUUCAAUUCCAUUUUUCAAUUAAUAGGUGAAAUUUUAUUCAUGCUUUGAUAGAAAUUAUGUCAAUGAAAUGAUUCUUUUUAUUUGUAGCCUACUUAUUUGUGUUUUUCAUAUAUCUGAAAUAUGCUAAUUAUGUUUUCUGUCUGAUAUGGAAAAGAAAAGCUGUGUCUUUAUCAAAAUAUUUAAACGGUUUUUUCAGCAUAUCAUCACUGAUCAUUGGUAACCACUAAAGAUGAGUAAUUUGCUUAAGUAGUAGUUAAAAUUGUAGAUAGGCCUUCUGACAUUUUUUUUCCUAAAAUUUUUAACAGCAUUGAAGGUGAAACAGCACAAUGUCCCAUUCCAAAUUUAUUUUUGAAACAGAUGUAAAUAAUUGGCAUUUUAAAGAGAAAGCAAAAACAUUUAAUGUAUUAACAGGCUUAUUGCUAUGCAGGAAAUAGAAGGGGCAUUACAAAAAUUGAAGCUUGUGACAUAUUUAUUGCUUCUGUUUUCCAACUACAUCACUUCAACUAGAAGUAAAGCUAUGAUUUUCCUGACUUCACAUAGGAGGCAAAUUUAGAGAAAGUUGUAAAGAUUUCUAUGUUUUGGGUUUUUUUUUUUCCUUUUUUUUUUUAAGAGUAUAAGGUUUACACAAUCAUUCUCAUAAUGUGACGCAAGCCAGCAAGGCCAAAAAUGCUAGAGAAAAUAACGGGAUCUCUUCCUUGUAAACUUGUACAGUAUGUGGUGACUUUUUCAAAAUACAGCUUUUUGUACAUGAUUUAGAGACAAAUUUUGUACAUGAAACCCCAGAUAGACUAUAAAUAAUUCUAAACAAACAAGUAGGUAGAUAUGUAUGUAAUUGCUUUUAAAUCAUUUAAAUGCCUUUGUUUUUGGACUGUGCAAAGGUUGGAAGUGGGUUUGCAUUUCUAAAAUGGUGACUUUUAUUCUGCAAGAGUUCUUAGUAACUUCUUGAGUGUGGUAGACUUUGGAACAUGUAAAUUUUUUGCUUGUAAUGUUAUCCUGUGGUAGGAUUUUGGCAGGUACACACACUGCCCUAUUUUAUUUUGAGUCUAAGUUAAAUGUUUUCUGAAAAGAGAUACAUGCACUGAACUCUUUCCACUGCGAAUCAAGAUGUGGUAAUAUAAAAGGAUCAAGACAAAUGAGAUCUAAUACUACUGUCAGUUUUAAUGUCCACUGUGUUUUAUACAGUAUCUUUUUUUGUUCACUUUGGAAAUUUUUACUAAAAAUUGCAAAAAAUAAAGUAUUGUGCAAAGAUGUAAGGUUUUUUGAAACUUGAAAUGCAUUAAUAAAUAGACGAUUAAAUCAACUUGAAGGUUCUAUACUCUUUGAACUCUGAGAACUAUCACAAGAAGCUUCCCACAAGGCAGUGUUUUCUUACAGUUGUCUCUUCCUACAAAAGUAUAGAUUAUCUUUAUUCUUAAUACUUUGGAAUCCAUGUAGAAAAUUUCCAGUUAGAUACUCUGCGUACACACAAUAAACCUUUUUAAAACACCCAACUAAUCUCAACUGCAUUACAUUGUUUCUAAUCAAUAUUCAGUGCUUGUCUUGGUGGAAGAGGUGAGUCAUUUUGAAAACUUAUGGUCUUGUUUUUAUGUGUUUUUCAAAGUUUUGAAUGCUAAGUACCUCAUUUAUUUUAAAAAGCCUAGUUUAAUGAUAAGUUUGUUUAAAAUUUUGAGCCAUCAUUUUUCUCUUCAUAGCAAAUAAGGAGAGAAUUGACAUUUCAGUGUUACCUAGAAAAGGAAUUGUAAGCCCAGAAUAAUUCCCUGCAUGAGGUAAUCUGCUUCAAAUUCUUUUUUUAGUCAAGGUUAGCUAUAAGUAAUACUUGUUAAAUGAGUAAAUAUGUAAUACUUUGUGAAUUACUUUGUUAAUUUAGGAGCAUCAAAUGUAUAUUAUGUUUAGUUAUUUAUGAAACUCUCAAUAUUGAUUGAUUUGGGUAAUUAUAAAUUAGUUAUUUUUACUUGUAAUUGAAUGCUUAAAUUCUGUUUACAGUCCGUCCUCUCUCCCUCCAUCCCUCCCUCCCCAGUUUUAUAAAUUCAGGUACCAAUUCACAAACAAAAUCAGAAAUAAAAUAAAUUUAUUGACUGCUUCUGGAUUUAGCAUUCCCUGUAGUGUCAAGCAAUGUCAUGCAGUUUGGGGAAGCAUUUAUUUAAGGAAAUGACAACUUUCUCUGAUCAGUCUUGUUUUGUGAGGUGUCUUCAACACUUUAUGCUUUGGGUACUUCGUGUUUGUCACAGUCUUAGGAUAGUGAAAUCUGAUUUGUCCAAGCGGAGCAAACUACUCGACCCUCAGUCCUUGUAUUUGUCCCUGUAGUAAGACCUAAUUAUUAUUAUUUCUUAAAGAUGGGAUUGGUGUCCUUGGCAACUAUGAAAUUUCGGGGCUUGUGCAUGAGAAGGCAUUUCUUAUUAAGUAUUUCUAAUUGAAGGUAUCAGAGUGUCAAGCAUUACAAACCUGGACAGUUCACCUGGAGGAGUACAAGAAGAGAUAUUCAUUAUCCAUAUUUAAAGGGUCAAGGUUUCCCAAAACCAGGGUGCAAGCCAGAUGUAGUUUUAAAGCAGCUGCCAGGGACAGUUCAUCUUUAGAGAAGUCACUAAAGUUGUAAGAAAUUUUAGUUUCCCCAAAACCACUUUCAACUUCUUAGAAACUAGAAAGACAAUUGGUUUGCCCCACAGAGGACAACUUCAGUUUCAGCAUCUCUCAUGUUGUGUUCUUGAUUAAAAACAACUUCCAUUUGAUAUACUUUUCCGUUUAUUACCAGUUUAGUUUUUUCACUAUUGUUUCUGUAUUCAACUCUUUAUAUGAUUAGGAUAGAAAUUUAGCCCUUCUGUUUUAUAUUACUAUAUUGUUUGUGUGUCUUAGAUAUAUACAUGUAUGUACUAUUUUCAGUAGAAAUUCAUGUAUUUUAUAAUUGGUAAGUUCUUCAGAGCAUCUCUUCUAUAAAAAGCAACAGGAUGCUAGGUAAAACGGAGCAUUGAGCAAAAUACUGAUUAGUUUUUGCUUUUUCCUGAAAUCUACACUAAAGUGAUAGGGUGUGGGGUAAUCCAACAAGGACAAGGUGAAUUGAACAAGAACGAAAUCUGGAAGCAGAUGAAGGAGUACUAUUGAUUGGGCAGACCCAGGGAAGUCAAAUCCUAAACCAGCAGUGGGAACACAACAGAAUGGUGUAGUUUGCACUGGUAAGAUUUGGGUACCUGGCAGGGCUGGGUGCGGUGGCUCACACCUGUAAUCCCAGCACUUUGGGAGGCCAAGGCGGGUGGAUCACUUGAGGUCAGGAGUUCGAGACCACCCUGGCCAACAUGGUGAAACCCCGUCUCUACUAAAAAUACAGCUGGGCGUGGUGGCACAUGCUUGUAAUCCCAGCUACUCGGGAGGCAGAGGCAGGAGAUUUGCUUGAACCCGGGAGGCAGAGGCAGGAGAUUUGCUUGAACCCAGGAGGCAGAGGCUGCAGUGAGCCGCGAUUGCGCCAUUGCACUCCAGCCUGGGUGACAGAGCGAGACUCUGUCUCAAAAAAAAAAAAAAAAAAAAAAAAAAAAAAAAAAAAAAAAAAAAAAAAUUUGAGUACCUGGCCUUUGUUACUUUUUUUCUAUGUGUGUGACAAAAACAUAAUAUGCACACUUUUGUAACCCACCUUUCUCAUUUAAUGGUACAUUGAUAAUGUAUAUCACAUUAACUACUCUAAAUAUUUCUGUGGAUGUAUGUUUUUUUUUUUCUUAACCAAUUUCCCAUUGUUUGGACAUGUAGGUUCCACAUUGUUUAUUAUUUUAAACAAUUCUAAAGAAUUUUAAACAAUUCUUAGGAAAAUCCUCAGCCUAAUAAUGAAAUUAAUUCCUAAAAGUGGAAUUGUUGGGGUAAAGGUUUUUUGAGGGACAUUGAUAAAAAUUAUGGUACUGUCUCCCAGAUAGAUGUACCAAGUUAUACUACCACGAUUUAAUAUAUAUAUAUAUAUAUAUUAAAUCAGAGUCCCAUCCUUAGAAAUCCACAUAUAUGCAGCCACAUGAAUGUAUUAGAAACAAUAAUAGAAGACUCAUGCUUAAUUCAGUUGAUUAGCUUUAGACAUAAUUCAAAUGCAAGUCAAAUUGAGUGCCCUAAUUGUGGUCUCUUAAGUACCAUUUUUCUUCAAGGGAACCAGACUCCUUUGGAUAAAUCACUAAUUCCACCUGUAAGAAAGAAAUGUACAAGAAGAACCUAGGAAACAUUGUUUUGUACCAGAUCAGAAAGAUUCAGGAGGCACCUUAGAAGUUACCACUGGCCAAGGCUGAGAUAACUUUAGCAUCAGCAAGGAUAAUAUCUGCAAGAGAUUGAAACUCAUAGUAUUGUAUUUAACUCUGUGAGUUAAUGAUGGUAGUGGACAGAAUUAUAGUUACCUUUGGGAUACGCUUUUAAAGAAAUUCCAGGUAAUAAGAGAAAUGAUAGAAUUAGGAUAUCACCAUUUUACCCCCCCAACAAUUUAUGGAUCUAGACAAUAAUCGCCAGUGACUGCUAACCUCACAAAGUGAGAGCAAUCAGAUUUUGUGCCUCCUAAUGGAAGUACAUAUACCACCUAUGAAGCAGUUCUGCCAAAAGUCACAUCUCAUCAUGAUGAAGCCUCCUGAUCUAACUACCCCUUCAUUAGAAAUACAGGGGACAGAGGGACAAAUAAUAUACAAGGGACUCAAUCAGCAAAAUCCAGACUCUGGAAAACUACAAGACAUAUGGUCCUGCUUCAACAACAGAAAUGCAAAGAGAAAAGACAACGAUGGGUUAAAGGAGACUUAAGAGCUACAUCUAUCAAGACAAUUUAUGGACUUAUUUGGAUACUGAUUUGAACAAACUGUUGAGACCAUUGGAAAAAUGUGAAAAGUGGAUAUUUGAUAUUAAGGUUUUUAAUUAUUUUUAGGUGUGAUAAUGGUAUUGUUACAUUUUUUAAAGGACCCCUUUUAGAGAUGCAAAUUGAAACACUUAAAAAAUGAAAUGAUACGAUGUAUAAGUUUUUGCUUAAAAAUAAGGAUUGAAGUUGGCUGGUGUGUGUGGAUAUAGUUGAAACAAGAUUGGCUGUGAGUUGAUAAUUAUUGAAGCUGGGUGAUGGGCACUUGGGGAUUUAUUAUACUAUUUUCUCUACCUGUGUUUAUAUUUGAAAUUUUUCAUAGAAGUUUUAAAAUGUGGCCAGUUGUGAUGGCUCAUACCUGUAAUCCCAACACUUUGGGAGGCCAAGGUGGGAGGAUCACUUGAGCUCAGGAGUUAGAGACCAGCCUGGGCAAAAUAGUGAGACUCCAUCUCAAAGAAAAAAAAAAAGUGUUUUAAAUGUGAAUCAAAUUCCUAUAGAAGCUGAUUCAUUACUGUUUUUAUUUUAGCAGUAAUUCAUGAUAAUGACCUGUAUUCAUAAUGAUUUUCAUAAUGAUUGUUUUAGUGGAAUUAAACUUGAACCAGUCAAGCUAACAUAAUUAUAUUCUGCUCCAGUUACAAUGAAUAAUUAAUUGAUUUCAACUGCUAGGGUGAACUCUUGAAGCUAUCAGUCAUCCAGCAAUCUUAGCAAGCAGGCCAUUGGGUCCCUGUUUGCUCUGUCUCUCUCUCUCUCUCUCACUGUUGAAGGGCUUAGCUAACUACUUAAGUAAAAUAUUUGUUCUCUGUUAAACAUGUCAAGGAGUAUGGUCAGCUUAUCCACAUUAAGCCUGUGUGUCCCACGUUGGAGUAAAUGUUAAGUAGCUCACUACAAUAAACUAGAUUCUUCUGCCCUCUCUUGUUUAAAUGAUCAUGUUCCCUGGAGGUGGAAAUAGAUCUUUAAAAAGAUAUUCUGUAGUUGUUUGUUCUCAGUGUAAAAAAAUGAGAAUAAUUUGAUAAGAGUGUAGGUUGUCUUAUAUAAAAAGUGGUUCCAUUUGCAUGAAUUUUAGAAAAAUCAUUUUGGAAAAAUGAAGGCUAUGUGGUUAUACUGAACACAUUAAGCAAUUUUAUUCUUUAUUUUAAAUGAAUAUUUUAUUAUCGUUUUCUUCCCUUGCCCUUUGGGUAUGGGAGUUAGCCUUUGUGUUUCUAAAUACAACAGGCCGGUUUUUAUAAAUUAAGGUGUCAAUAUAUUCUUCAUUAUUUAGUUUUGUGAUUGUGGUUAGUUUUCAUUUUUCUUAAGUAUCUGCUAGUAGCAUCUGUAAUUAAGUGAAGUGACCUGUUAACCAUUUUCCUCUUUCUCCUCCUUUCCUCCUCCUUGAAACAUAUCAGAGCAUGUUUGAAAUUCUUUGGCUUUUAUGGUAUGCAUUUGCUGAUAUGCAUUGACCAGUUACCUUACUCACAGAUACUUCUUAGGCACUUGAUUGUGCCAGGGCCUUGGCUAGAUGAUAAGAAUACAGUAGUGAACUUAACAGUUUCCCUGCCCUGGUGAAGCGUAUGGUCUUGUAGGUGAGAUAGAUAUCAGAUAAUCAUGUGAAUAAAUGUACAAUUCCAGCUGUGAUACAUGCUGAGGAGGAGGUUUUUGGUGAUCCAAGAGCUGAUCAUGCAGAGAUAGGACUGAGAAAGGAGGGUGGGACGUUGUCACAGCUGAUAAUGCAGAGAUAGGACUGAGAAAGGAGGGUGGGACAUCAGGAAGGUCAGAGAAUUCCUUAUGAAAGUGAUGCUUGAGUCAAAAUAUGAUGGAUGAAGAGAGUUUAAAUAGAUUACAUAGAAUUUUUAAUAAUGUCGAUUGGUUAUAUACUGGGCACUGAUAGCUGAUUUUUCUUUGGGGAAAGGUAUGUCAGCCUAGUCAUUCAGAUUCCUUUAUUUUUUUAAAUGUUUUUUCAUUUUUUGCUUUGCAUUGCAUUCAUUUGCUGAAGAGCUGGCUUGUACUUUGGCAGGUGUCAUACUUGGUUAUUCUCCUUAGGAUAUUGGCCCAACAAUCUGGGAGUUGUGAAAGGCGCUUCGCUUUUCAGACCUGGGCGUCUGUAUCAUGACUAUCAUAAAUUUAGGAUUAAGACACCUAGCCUCCUACCAGGAUGAAUGAGGUGUCCAUGUGACCUGCUGUGCCCUGGAAUUUUAUACAUCUUUCUCUCAUAGCACACACCAUAUUACAAUAUAAUCCUGCCUCAUCUAAGCCAAACUUUCGAGAGAAUCAUUUACACUCAGUGGCUACUUCAGCUCCCAUUCACUUAUCAACCUGCUGCAAUUUUUCACAGCCCCCAAAGGACUGCAGUCUGUGCCUUCAGGGAGCUGAGGGUCUAGCGGAAGGAAAGAAACCAGCAGUUACAGUACAGAGGGGUUUGUGUUGGAAACUCUACAAACACAGGAUGCCCUGGUAGCUCAGAGGAAGUGCAUAUCGAGCAUGGUAGGUAGGUAGUGGGAAGAGCCAAGAUGACUUCCCAGAGGAGAAAAGCUGGACCUGAGUUUUGGAGUUUCGGUAAAAGUUUGCUCUAACUAGUCCAAGCUGCUGUCACAAGCUUUUAGAAAUGAUGUAACCAUGGGGCAGUUGACUGUCGUCAUGUUCUUUGCUAUUUUCAUGACUCUGGAUGUGCUUUUCCUAUUCCCUGGAUUGCCCUUUCCCUCGAUUCCUCUGCAGGACUGGGCUUUAUUAAUCUCCAUUUCCUUGAGCUUGGCUAUAGUAGGUGUUCAAUAAACAUUUGUUUUGUUGUGUGCUUUGUAAAUAGGCAAUGAAGCUGAUUUCACAAGAUAGGCACAAAAGUUAGUUUCAUUACAACACAUUACCAACAGCUGUAUUUUUAACUUUUAACAUAUCUCAUUCUAAAUCCUGUGGCAGCACAACCUCCUUCCGUCAUACCUGGAGAUAAAUUUUCUUUCAAAAUCUAAUAUGCACUGUAUUUAUAGAAUAUGAAACAUACCGACCAUGUUUUGCAAAAAUGGGAAAGGCAUAACUUAGCUUUGGGGCAUGUAAGUAACAACUCCUGAUAGGAGAAGAAAUGUAUUCAGAAAGCUCAAAUUAGAAAUAAAAUGGGAGACUCUA